AGAGCCCAGGCCGGUCGGCCGGGCCCGCGUGCCCUCGGCGGGCUGCGCAGAGCGCGGGAGCGGUUUGGGGCUGGGCAUGCUGGGAGCCCCUCGGGCAACGGCCGCCGCCGCCACAGCCACACAGCCGCCGCCACUGCGUCCGUCCCCGGUGAGCGCCGCUGACGCGCGGAGAUGAAAUUCCCGGCCUCGGUGCUGGCGUCCGUGUUCCUGUUCGUGGCCGAGACAACGGCGGCGCUCAGCCUGAGCAGCACCUACCGCUCGGGCGGGGACCGCAUGUGGCAGGCGCUGACGUUGCUUUUCUCGCUACUGCCUUGCGCGCUCGUGCAGCUCACGCUUCUCUUCGUACACCGCGACCUCAGCCGCGACCGCCCGCUCGUACUGCUGCUGCACCUGCUGCAACUUGGGCCCCUUUUCAGGUGUUUUGAAGUCUUCUGCAUCUACUUUCAGUCAGGCAACAAUGAAGAGCCUUAUGUCAGUAUCACCAAGAAGAGGCAAAUGCCAAAAAAUGGCCUCUCAGAGGAGAUUGAGAAGGAGGUGGGCCAGGCAGAAGGCAAACUAAUCACCCACCGAUCAGCGUUCAGCCGGGCGUCGGUGAUCCAGGCUUUCUUGGGCUCAGCCCCCCAGCUGACCCUACAGCUGUACAUAAGUGUCAUGCAGCAGGACGUCACUGUUGGAAGAAACCCUGUGCUGGUCUCUGAGGAUAAAGUGGUGAAUAAGGUAGGCAGGCCCCAAUCAUCUUCAAAUAGGAUAUAUAAACAUCACACAAAUUAUUAAUCAAAUGCAUAUUUUAUUUAAGGUAAAUCCUGCAAAGUGAAAGAUAAGUAGCCUCUCUGAGGGUAUAUUGGGGGUUGUCUAACCGAGUCUGGGAAAUGAGGCAAAUGUUUCCAAAACUUAGAUUUAAACUGAAAACUGCUAGAUGAAGAAAAGAAGCCAGGUGAAGAAAAAUCAGGAAAGAGCAUCCCAGGAUUUCAAGCUUUAUUCCAGAGGCAAUGGGAAGGCACUGAUGAGUUUUAAGCAACAAGUGUCAUGAUCAAAUUUAGUUUUAGAAACUGAUUACUCUGCAAAAUGUAUUUGAAGAGAGUGAAGAAACAAAUGGAGAGGCUAGGAAGUGGGCUACUAUAGUUGUCAAGGUGAGAAUAAUGGCCUGGACUGGAAUAGUCAGAGUGGAUUAUUGGAGCAAUAUUAAGAAUGCGUAAGUGGAACAAUGUGAUGAUUGAUUGGAUAUGAAGGUGAGGCAGUGAGAGAUGUCAAGAAUAAUUCCCAGUUCCUGAUAUGGACUGCUGUAGCCAUGGAUCUCCAUUUGUCUUGGUAGUGACAGGUUUGCGAGGUAUAUUUUACUUUCAGUUCCAGACUUAAAGAAAUGAAUACAUUUUAAAGAUUCUAUUUAACUCAUGAGAGAACAAGCAGAUGUUCUCUUCGGACCAGCUUAUAAGAUAACCCAAAGGACAGACAUAGGAAUAUUGACUAGAGAUAUCAAAAUGAAUAUGUAAAUGGAAGUAAAACUGGUUUUAUUACAGCAUGGGGGGGUGACAUUUGAACCUCUACUGUACAAGACAUUGAGCAUGUCUGUUAGUGACUUAUAGCUUACAGAAGAAUGUAAAUGAGCUCACUGGCAAUACAAAGCUAGAAUCAGAGAACCUGGAUUGGUAUACUGAAGACAGGACAAUGUUUUGAUUGAAACACAUUUUUUUUGUUGUUGCUAGAAUGUUUAAGUCAAGUACAAAGUUAGACUUUCCUCAAAAAGACGGUCCAGUUAUUAGGGUGAGCAGGUUCCUGUCAGAAACAUUUUGAGGCCGGGCUUGAUCAGGGCUCAGUGAACACCAAUAAUAUCACAAAGUUGAGGUUGUCUUGAAGGCAGCUCCCUGACCAAGGAGGGCCUGGAGCACAGUGGGCGGGAAUAAGCACUGGUACCUGGAGAGGCUCAGGCUAGUGGGAAAAUCGACGAGGGCUGAUCAAAACAAAACUCACCAAGACCAUGUGAAGGCAAAAAGGAGCCUUAGAAAGGAGAUUCUUCCCUGCUCCACAAAAGCCUAGCUGCAGUUUCCUGUUAGCCACAUGGACGGCUUUCUGCGAGGUCAGUAUGCCCAGUGCCUGAGCUCAUCCACACCUGUUUUCCUGGUUGUUAUUCUCUAGUAUCUGAUGGCCAACAUCCUGGAGCAGGCAGGCAAGAAGGCCCAGAACAAUUGCAGGGUGCGCAUCACACCAGAACACAUAGAGAGGGCCAUGCACAAGGAUAAGCAGCUCAGAUGCCUCUUGGAGGAUGUACCCACCAUCAGGUUGAUGAGGUGCCCCAGCCCGAGAAGGAGGGAUGCUUGGGUCUGAGAACCUGGCAGGACUUCAUCAACAAUUUCAUCCAGCCUCAAAAAUUCCCAUAGAUGAGAGACCCCAGGCUGCUGCCAUCAGCCCAUGCUAUUAAAGUCUUUAAUGACAGUGCCCCUGACUUCUCUCAGGUUCUCUCAUUUUGGGUUGGAGGUGUCCUUGAGACAUCCAGGAGAAGCUAUCCCAUAGAGAGCUGAAUGGGUGGAAGGUGUUGCCAGUGUGGGGUGUUUGAAUCAGUGAUUUUAGAAGGGGCAGUUUCCAGUGGUUGGUGAGAGCACUGGCCCUGGCGGGAGGAGCUGACUGGGGAUAAAGAUAUAGAGACUUCCUCAUUGGCUUUGAACUGGAAGGCCUUGUGAGGCCAGGUAGUUGCUGGGAGCCUCCUAGGCUUGAUAAAUUCCUAACCUGAUGCUGGGACCUAGGGUGGAGCUGCAGACUCUGACUGAGGUGCGGGAGGCUUUAUUCAGAAUAGCAAAGGUCUGAAGUCAGAGGGCAGUAGCCACAGGGAUGGGUGGAGAGGGGGCACACUGCAUACUAGCUGGCAUGAACUUCAUGGGACAGGCUUUACAUGGAGAUUGAGGAGUGAUGGGGAAAACAUAAGGAAAAAAUGCAAAAAAAAAAGUUAUGGUCAUGUUAUUUUAUUUAUUUAUUUGUACCCUGCCUCAUUCCAAAAGAGGACUUGAGACAGGGAUUAGUAACUGGUACUAUGACACAUUGUUUGGAAUAUAUUCUUCUGUCCUCUUGUGGACACUGUUAAAUUAAGUAGUAACAUUAUAUAAAAGCUCUCUGGCCUAGGACAUGCAAUCCAAUCAGUUCUUAAUGGUUACAAAAUAUUACAAAACUUAUUUGUAAAUGUAUUCCAUUAUAAACACAAUUAUCAAUCGCAUUCCCAGAAAAAAUAAUCUGUGUAUGAUCAUGUAUUUCAUAGAACAGCAUAGAGUUAUCAAUGGCCAAAAACAGGUUCAAAAGGUAUAGAAAUAACCUAUGUAAUUCUGUCUUGAGUGAUGGCCUCUAAAGCAUGUACUGUACUUUUAAAAACUUGUGCUCUGUACUGUUUAAAAAAGGUGUCACAUCAAGUGUUGUAGCAAUCUGUCCCCUUGCCUGUGAAUGUCCAUAUUUUAGGUUUUCACCUGUUCCUUGGAUCCUCUGUGGCCACAUUCUGCUGCCUGUUGGCCAGAUGCUGCCCAGCCAGAUUCAAUAACAGAUCAGACAACCUGGGUUUGAGAUCCUAGUUCACCACUUUCUGGCCAUGUGAUCUUGGACUUUCAUUUACUCCUGCUGGGCAGGUUUGCUCAUGUGUAAAAUAGCAGAGAGUCCCUCUAUCUUUAGUUUUCCCAAAGAUUGAGUCCACUUUGGAUAUGCACAGUGUGGCCCUUAAUAAGCAGCUGCAUCUGUCUCCUCCCCUAACCCCAGACACGCAGGCAGGCUUCCCCAGGGUACAUCUGGGUCUGGUUCUCAGGUUACUGUUGGGCACUUGGGCCACUGGCUGUGAGAGUGACAUCCUGCUGAGCCCUAUGGAGAGACAGGAGAGUGCCCAGCAGAGGAAGGAGACAGCGGAAGAGGGACACGAGCCAGGCAGUCCCCACUCUGGUGUCCCUUUUUCUCCUCCUGCCUUGUGACUCGCCCUCUCUCUGCCUCUGUCUAAGCAGAAGGACCCAGCUUGGCCUUUGGCUAAUUCACAGGAGUGUCCUGAGAAUGAAGGAAAUAGCGGUUAUGUGUUUAAAAACUGGGCUGUGAGAAACCCAUGUCCUGGACACAAAGAUGUUUCACUUCGGCCAGGGGAGGGGGUGCUGCUGUUGCCAUGAAGUGAUGAGCUGAAGGAGACUCCCCACCUGAAGCUGCUGGAGAGAGGCCUGCUUGCAGCUCAAAUGCACAGAAGAGGAAGCGAGCAGCUGGGCUAAGGCUGGGAGUGCUCCACGGCGCUCCCUAAGGAAUCAUGCAGUGGUGGGGUGGGCAGCUUGACAAUGAGGUGCCUGGAAAUAUGAGGUUCAGUGGACAUGAUAUGGCAAGAAAGACUUCUGGGAUUUAGACAAGCACAUCUUCCACAUGGCCCUAAGGACAACCCUGACAGUACUAAUCUCUAAUAUAUUAUUUCCUAAAGCGCAGUCUACAAAGUGGCAUCUUACAACUCAAUCUGGAUGGCAGAUAGGUUUGCUAGUUCUAAGCAGACAUCUUAAAAGAAAAUUAAUGAGCUGGUAGCAUUUGAAAAUCAAUAACAUUUUACCUGAAAGUCUGGAUUUCUGGCUCUCUUGAGAAGUAAAAAGGAGGGUACACAUGAUUACAGUCACAUAGAGAUGACUAGCUACUGCACCAUGAAGACUGGGCCUCUGGUUUGCCACAUUCCUUCCACACUCUUCCCUAUAAAGUCCCAUAUCUGAUUCACUUCAUUAAUUUAUAGUAGUUGUCUGAUUAAUAGAGAUACUUGAGUUUGUUACUCUCACUACAAGUUAAUUCUAAGUUCACAGUACUCAGAACAAUCAAUCUCAUUUAAUGAAGUAGUAUAUUGUGCAUUGCUUCUCAAAAUAUCAUUGGGGUAGGACCAGUAGUAGCAAACUUCCUUGUUUUUCUUGUUCCAGUAAAUUGUGAACUGAUAUGUGGUUGUAUUACUAGUAUGCCACUCAUAUUUGACUUGUCAUUUGAGUUUAACAACUGCACUGGUAUAUACCUUGUUCAAAAAGUGAGCCCACUAAUUUAAAUGUUGUGGCUAAAUCAGAUGCUAUACAGAUUCCUAAAUGCCAGCUCUCAAUGUCCAUACUUAUCAUAACUGACUGGUAACAGAUAUUUCAUUGUACCAGUCCUCAAACUUUUUAGAUUUAGAUUUAGAUUUUAAAUCUAAUGAAAAGCAGUAAACAGGACCUACAGUUGGUAUUGUUUCUCCUUCAGAGUCUUCAUGAAAACAGAUUUAUCCUUCUUAUAUUUAGGACUUUAGCAUAAUACUGGUGAAAAUGUUGCUGAACUACUUCUGUUAAAGCAAAAGAUAUUAAGGAAACCAAUUAGCAUCAGUGGGGCAUGUUAGAUGCGGCAGAUGUGAGAUUGUUGAGUUCUGAAAUGUAGGAUAAAAAGAAUUCACCAAGGCAACUGUGAAAGGGAGUCUUCAUGAAAGGAGAGGCAGAACUGGGUUCUGGUCUCCUACAGUGUAGUUUACUUGGGGACCCAUCAGUUUCCAGUGAGAAAAAUGGAAAAAUUAUUUCAAAACUCAGCUAGAGAUGUGUACUUAUGACUGUGCUCUUUUCCUAACAAAAUAGUUCUAUGGAAAAUGGGUAAAUAGGGUUCAGAGUACAGGGUCUCCAUUUUACAGCUGAGGCCACUGAGGCCCAGUGAUAGUAAUCAGCUCUUAUAAAGUCACAUGGUGAGUGGGCAGCACAGUAGAAUGAUGGCCUGGCCUUCCUUACCUGUUAUUGGGGCUCUUUCCUCUAUUGUAUCCUGAAAAAGGGGUCUCAAAAGAGAAAGUGUUUAAUGUUCUCCUCUGAGAAAAAGAAGCUAAAGUCUUCAAUACCAAGGUGUUAGGGUCUCUUGGAUUUCUUGGGAAGCACUCAAUAACUCACUCCCAAGAAUAUUCACUUGUGCUUUAUUUGGGUAAGGCCAGACAGGUCAGGAGAAAAGUGCUGAUUUUAUAGUAUAGGUCUUUGGACUUUGCAAACUUAGAUUUUGUUCCACUGGACAUUGUAUUAAACUGUGUUAUGAACACAAAUUUGUCUCAGUUAAGGUGUUCUGGAAAUUCUGACUCUGUCCACUAACCAUUAUCUUAAAUGUGGUGAUGUGAUGUCAUGAGAAGCCUGUGUUCAGGAGCCUAGUCUUUGAAGUACCUGAGGUAGUGACGUUUUUCAUGGUGCUCUAAGACAAUCCUUCUUUGCUGAAGACAAAAUCUCCCUCCUGUAGCUGAUUGUAGGGUCAUUAGGGAAACAUCAGUGUAAAUAAAAAACUAUCUGGAGAGCCAGGCAUGCUGGCUCAUGCCUGUAAUCCCAGCAACUUAGAAGGUUGAGGCAAG